GAGGCUGGCGGGCGCGGGGAAAAUGGCGGCGGCGGCGGCGGCGGCUGCAGCUACGAACGGGACCGGAGGAAGCAGCGGGAUGGAGGUGGAUGCAGCAGUAGUCCCCAGCGUGAUGGCCUGCGGAGUGACUGGGAGUGUUUCCGUCGCUCUCCAUCCCCUUGUCAUUCUCAACAUCUCAGACCACUGGAUCCGCAUGCGCUCCCAGGAGGGGCGGCCUGUGCAGGUGAUUGGGGCUCUGAUUGGCAAGCAGGAGGGCCGAAAUAUCGAGGUGAUGAACUCCUUUGAGCUGCUGUCCCACACCGUGGAAGAGAAGAUUAUCAUUGACAAGGAAUAUUAUUACACCAAGGAGGAGCAGUUUAAACAGGUGUUCAAGGAGCUGGAGUUUCUGGGUUGGUAUACCACAGGGGGGCCACCUGACCCCUCGGACAUCCACGUCCAUAAGCAGGUGUGUGAGAUCAUCGAGAGCCCCCUCUUUCUGAAGUUGAACCCUAUGACCAAGCACACAGAUCUUCCUGUCAGCGUUUUUGAGUCUGUCAUUGAUAUAAUCAAUGGAGAGGCCACAAUGCUGUUUGCUGAGCUGACCUACACUCUGGCCACAGAGGAAGCGGAACGCAUUGGUGUAGACCACGUAGCCCGAAUGACAGCAACAGGCAGUGGAGAGAACUCCACUGUGGCUGAACACCUGAUAGCACAGCACAGCGCCAUCAAGAUGCUGCACAGCCGCGUCAAGCUCAUCUUGGAGUACGUCAAGGCCUCUGAAGCGGGAGAGGUCCCCUUUAAUCAUGAGAUCCUGCGGGAGGCCUAUGCUCUGUGUCACUGUCUCCCGGUGCUCAGCACAGACAAGUUCAAGACAGAUUUUUAUGAUCAAUGCAACGACGUGGGGCUCAUGGCCUACCUCGGCACCAUCACCAAAACGUGCAACACCAUGAACCAGUUUGUGAACAAGUUCAAUGUCCUCUACGACCGACAAGGCAUCGGCAGGAGAAUGCGCGGGCUCUUUUUCUGAUGAGGGUACUUGAAGGGCUGAUGGACAGGGGUCAGGCAACUAUCCCAAAGGGGAGGGCACUACACUUCCUUGAGAGAAACCGCUGUCAUUAAUAAAAGGGGAGCAGCCCCUGAGCACCCCUGCUGGUGGCUCUGUCCUCUGUUAGGCACCACACUGGUUGGUCAACUUGGAUGUUCAUCGAGGCUCAUUCUGGCCUUGCUCAGAAGCCCUUCUGAUGCUCUUCAGUGAGGGAGGCACUACCAUUUGAAGUGACCCCAUGUCAGUCACAUGGACUGGUCUUUAGCAAAGUCCAAGGCUGCCUGCUUCCACCUAAGUGGUCUCUGUUCUACACUUUAAUGUCACCCUCUACAUCAUCUUACCUAGCCCACCCAACCUUAUAAACAUGAUAAUUGACUACU